GAAACCCGGGUUGAGGCAGGAGGCGGCUAGACCGGUGGCGGCGGCAUCUGGAGUAGCACUGAGAUCUUCCGGUGGCGGGAACUGCAGUCAUGGAUCAUAUUACGGUACCCAAGGUAGAAAACGUGAAAUUGGUGGAUCGUUAUGUGAGUAAGAAACCAGCUAAUGGGAUUCUUUAUCUUACUGCAACCCACCUGAUCUAUGUGGAGGCUUCAGGUGCAGCCCGGAAAGAAACAUGGAUUGCACUCCAUCACAUUGCCACUGUGGAGAAGUUACCCAUCACUAGCCUGGGUUGUCCCCUGACCCUCCGCUGCAAGAAUUUCCGGGUGGCCCACUUUGUUUUAGAUUCUGACCUUGUGUGCCAUGAGGUUUAUAUUUCACUGCUCAAGCUUUCUCAGCCAGCAUUACCUGAAGAUCUUUAUGCUUUUUCUUAUAAUCCCAAAUCCUCAAAAGAGAUGAGGGAAAGUGGAUGGAAACUGAUUGACCCAAUAUCAGACUUUGGGCGUAUGGGAAUACCCAACAGAAACUGGACCAUAACAGAUGCCAACAGAAACUAUGAGAUAUGCAGCACCUACCCUCCUGAAAUAGUGGUUCCUAAAUCUGUUACCUUGGGAACGGUGGUUGGAAGUUCAAAGUUCAGAAGUAAAGAACGUGUCCCUGUGCUCUCCUACCUCUACAAAGAGAACAAUGCUGCCAUUUGCCGCUGUAGCCAGCCUCUCUCUGGAUUUUACACUCGCUGUGUAGAUGAUGAGCUCUUGUUGGAGGCCAUUAGCCAAACAAACCCAGGGAGCCAGUUUAUGUAUGUUGUAGACACAAGACCAAAGUUGAAUGCCAUGGCCAACCGAGCAGCUGGGAAGGGGUAUGAAAAUGAAGACAACUAUGCCAACAUUCGCUUCAGAUUCAUGGGCAUUGAGAACAUCCAUGUAAUGCGGAGCAGUCUGCAGAAACUCUUGGAAGUUUGUGAAUUGAAAACUCCAACAAUGAGUGAAUUUCUUAGCGGCCUGGAGAGCUCAGGGUGGUUAAGACACAUUAAAGCUAUUAUGGAUGCUGGAAUUUUCAUUACAAAGGCAGUGAAGGUAGAAAAGGCCAGUGUCUUAGUCCAUUGUUCUGAUGGAUGGGACCGCACAGCACAAGUCUGCUCAGUGGCUAGCAUCCUCCUAGAUCCAUUUUAUAGGACAUUCAAAGGACUCAUGAUCUUGAUAGAGAAGGAAUGGAUAUCCAUGGGCCACAAGUUUUCCCAAAGGUGUGGCCACCUCGAUGGGGACUCUAAAGAAGUGUCCCCUAUCUUCACCCAGUUCCUAGACUGUAUCUGGCAAUUAAUGGAACAGUUUCCCUGUGCCUUUGAGUUUAAUGAAAACUUCCUGCUGGAGAUUCAUGACCAUGUUUUCUCCUGCCAGUUUGGAAACUUCCUUGGUAACUGCCAGAAGGAUCGGGAAGAUCUAAGAGUCUAUGAGAAAACACAUUCUGUGUGGCCUUUCUUGGUUCAGAGGAAACCAGACUUCAGGAACCCUCUCUAUAAAGGCUUCACUAUGUAUGGGGUACUCAAUCCUAGUACUGUGCCCUACAACAUUCAGUUCUGGUGUGGGAUGUAUAACCGCUUUGACAAAGGGCUGCAGCCCAAGCAGAGUAUGCUAGAGAGCCUCCUGGAAAUUAAGAAACAGAGAGCAAUGCUGGAGACAGAUGUGCAUGAACUAGAAAAGAAACUAAAAGUCCGUGAUGAGCCACCAGAAGAGAUCUGUACCUGCUCUCAAUUAGGAAACAUAUUAUCCCAGCAUCUGGGAAGUCCUUUGACCAAUCCUCUUGGCUUUAUGGGUAUCAAUGGAGACCUGAAUACCCUGAUGGAGAAUGGCACCCUAUCCAGGGAAGGAGGCCUCCGAGCUCAGAUGGAUCAAGUAAAAAGCCAGGGUGCAGACCUCCACCAUAACUGUUGUGAGAUUGUGGGCAGCCUUAGGGCCAUAAAUAUCUCUGGGGAUGUGGGCAUCUCUGAGGCCAUGGGCAUCUCUGGAGACAUGUGCACCUUUGAGGCUACGGGCUUCUCCAAAGACUUAGGAAUCUGUGGGGCCAUGGACAUCUCUGAGGCCACUGGCAUCUCUGGAAACUUGGGUAUUUCUGAGGCCAGGGGUUUCUCUGGGGACAUGGGCAUCUUGGGGGACACAGGCAUCUCCAAGGCCAGCACCAAGGAGGCAGACUACUCCAAGCAUCAGUGAGUUAGUUACUCAUCUUCCAUGCUAGGUAUACCUACAGCAGCUACAAUGAUUCUUGUCCCAGAGAGGGCUAUGCUGCUUUUCCAAUUGGUUUAAGUGGGUGAAGCCAGGGCACCCCUCUCCCCACUUAAGUCUGGAAGGGAAUUACUUUACUGAUUAAGUGACCAAUAUGUUCAUAUUAAGCAGUACAGAGUGUAGGCAAGAGAAAGAAUAUGUUAUUGUUCUAAAAUGGGAUUUAACUAUAGAAAUGUUGCCUCUCAGCUGAGACACAUAUUAAGCUGGUUCUACUGUCUGUUUUCCUUAAUGAUCGACCUGCCCUAUUUUCUAUCCUCACUGCAGUAAUGUGAAAGUGAAGUGGAAAUAUUGUCACAAUGGUCAAUAAUGACCCUUUUGAGGGUAUGGAGAGAUGGUAUACAGCAGGUAACUGUGAAUUGCAGAAUAAAUUGAAAGAAAAUUUUA